AAAAACCAGAGAUGGACAUUACAAGAAAAACAAUUACAGGCCAAUAUCCCUGAUGAACAUAGAUGAAAAAUCAUCCACAACGUAGUUGCAAAUGAAAUUCAAAAGCACUUUAAAAGGAUCAUUUAUUAUGAUCAAGUUGGAUUUAUUCCUGGGAUGCAAUAAUAUUUUAAUAUGUGGAAAUCAAUAAAUGCCAUACUCCUUAUUUACACAACAAAAAGAUUAAAAAUCAUGACUUUUUUAUGCAUGCCUAAAAUUAUUUUGACAAAAUUUAAAAUCCAUUCCAAAUAAAAUCUAUAACAAAUUAGGUAUAGAAAGAAUAUACCUCAAAAUAAAGAGAUAUGUUCUUUAUAAGCUAUAGGACAAUCCCAUGGUUAACAUUAUUGUCAAUGGUGAAAUUUUGGAAUUAUUUUUAAGAUUUAUUAUAAGAAAAAGAUGCCCACUCUCACUACUUCUUUCAACACCGUAUUGGAAAUCCUGCUCAGAAUCUAAGACAAGAGAAAAAAGAGCAUUUAAAUAAGAAACAACAAGUUCUUCUAUUCAUGGAGAUUAACGCUCAGGUUUUUGCAGAUUAGAUUUAACAGCAUGAAAUCUGGUACCAUCCAGGAAUCAAAGGAUAUAGGACUUUAGGGCAUCAAUUAUUAAGAGGCUAUAGGAAAGCAGAAAUGCUCCUGGAUGUUUCCAUUGUCCACACACAAAAUUUCAACAGACCAGCCCCAGGAAGUAAAGGCACAUUCCUGACUACUGUUAGUUGAUGAGCUUUUCACCAAAAGCAGAGAUGUGAGACCUGGCAGGUUUCAAAGACCCCUCAAGUGCUCCAUACCUUGAAAUUCACUUCCACAAAGCUAGAACACCAUCUGUUCCUGAGGGAUCAGGUUAUCGUCUGUUUCUUUUAGGCACUGGCCAGUCAGGCUUUAGUGGACACGAAGCCACAGAUUUUUAGUGUAAAAUGCCUAAUCUAUCAUAAUCUUUAGGUAGAUAUUUGGAGGCCUGCACACUUAAAUGGGUUGGUGAAAUGUCAUACCAGACACAUGGCUGGGAAUUGGGUUUUUCUCCUCCGCUCUUAGCAGCACCUUUGUAACCCAGUGAUUACCCCCCUCAUGGCUCCACGGCCACAUCCGCAAAAAGGGUACUGGUGAACGUGACAUUUUCACGAAGCCACAGCCCAUGGUCACUCCCUGCAAAGCUCUGAACUUGCGCAUUCCCAGGCCAGGCCGUGGUUGUCUUUCCAAGGCGGCUCAGCUUGUGCUUUGCUUGGAGAGAGCGGAGGGCAGCAGCACAGUGACAGCGUCUGGGACCUCAGACCAGUUUCCACAGCCACUUAUGAAAGCAGACGGCUCCAUGGGCUGGAGGAGGUGGGACGCUCUGGAAAGAACUCGGGUGCAAGUGGGAAAGAAAAUCGAGCUGAGCAGCGGGAAGUCGAAGUCGCGUGAGUGAGGACCAGACACUCUCGAUUUAGGCAAAGGCGGGGUGCACUUCCCAACAACACAUCCUCCUCACUGGCGAGACCAGGCCUGCCCUUCAAGUUCCUCUCCUGAUUUAAUCCCCUUGGCGAGGGUUUGGCAUGAAAUCAAUGGCCAGCAAGCUUGGUAAACGAAGCCGCCUACACCGCCCUCCCCCUCCCUGCACGGCCGCGCCCCGCCUCCGCUCCUGUCUCAAUCUGGGAUUGUCCUCCUGUAGCCCCACCAUCCACCGUGGGGAACGGUGGAGAGACUACAACUCCCAGUAUGCACCGCGAUGCGCGCCUCACCCUGCAUCUCCCAGCCCGCAGCCAGCUGGCAUCCUAGACCCUCUGCCCUGCGACCAACAGCCGGGAGCGGACCAGACACCAGAACUCCCGGAACGGUUGAAGACGGUUCCGCUCCCUGUCCCGCCUUUCGCAGCCCAGCAGUUUCGCCCUGCGGAGAGGAGCCUUGCUGUUUCCAAAUCUCUCCUGCUGAAGAGACAUUGGAGCUAGGGCGGCUAGUUUCACCUGGUAAUUGUGACACCCUGUCUCCUCGAGCUGCAGGCUUUUAUGCUUGUCAUGUUCGAAGUUUGAUACCUUGCAGAUCAACAAAGGGUCGGUGGCCUCUCACUGCCUCCGCCGCAGGGUUGUCAAGACAUGCGCAGUGCGGCCCGUCCCUAGGGCUGGGUUAAGGGCCGCGGAUGUGGCAGUUCUCAGGCCUCUUGGGAUCGCCUCAAGAAGCCCCCUCACGAGUGUCUCGAUUUCCUGUCAGCCAACAAAGGGCCGUUCGCCUUUCAUGGCCUCCACAGCAGCGUUGCCGUGGCUGUCACAAAUCCUCUGCACCCCAGGAGUGCCGCUUGGACCCCCGGGCUCGCUGCGUGGUCCAUAUCUAGGUCGGGCCUCUCACGGAGACUUUCCCACCAGUGUAAUAAAGAGGAGAAAACGUCACAGCGGAAGGGCCUGACCCUGCUGCAUCCACUAAGGAAACAGCUACGGGGAUGGGACCCUGGAAGCUGCUGUGGGAGCCUCAUCCACCGCUUCUCUGACCCCACCCAGGCUGCUUCCCAGGCCUCAGGGUCUUAGUGUGGACCUCCGGGCCGUGAUUAAUGCAGUUUUUCAGGUUAAGUACUGCACGACUACUCGCUUCUGAAACUGAUAGACACUGCCUCAGCUCCGUGCAGGGCAGACGCACAAGAGCAGAAUCUCCGUGGGACAUCUCUCUGGAGCAUCAAUAUUACUGCAGUAUUUGGAAGAAACAAAUUUAAAUAAGUUCUAAGGUGAAGAAUGGAACAUUUAAGACAAGUCUGGAAAGUCAUCUGCCUUUAAUAACUGUCGUUUGUCCUUAACGUCAGACUUUCUCCAAGACCAAAACUCUAAGAACUUAUUUCCAUUCUUACAAAUAGUAAAAAUGAUAAAUCAUAUCAAGUCAAUUGAAAGUCCUGCCUGCUGCUUUCCUAAAUCACAAUAUGGCCUUGGUAUGGUUUUAUUUGUACUUUUGUGGGGGAUUCGUGGAUCUUUAGAUUAAAAAAAAAAAAUAGGUUUUUGAACAAUUUUUGCAAGUUUGCAGCUGUUAGUUAUUGAUUUAUUUUUGCAACCCAUCUAAUUCUUCUGUCUCUCUCCUCUCCUCAGGCUCAAUAAUUCCAUGGGUCUCUAAGGCUGUGUUUAUUUUCUUUAAAUUUUGUUGAUUUACUUUUAUACUCCAUUUGAUUUUUUCUAUCUCUCACCUUUUCUCAGACUCAGUCAUCCCACAGGUCUGUAAGGCUCUGUUCAUUUUCUUUAAACUUUUUUUUUUCCUCUCCUCAGAUUGGAUAAAUUAUAUUGCUAUGUCUCUGUUUCUGAACUAUAGAAAAGCUCAAAAUUACUAUUUUUAUUUCUCAUUUUUUAUAUGGCUAUUUUUUCUCUGCUGAUGUUUCACAUCUAUUCAUUUAUGAGAAUAUUUUCCUUUGCCCUCAUGAGCGUGUUUAUAAUAGCUGCCUUCAAAUUCUUGUCUGCCGUUUACAUCUUGGACAUCUUGGAGAUGGCUACUGCCUGCUUUUUAUCUUGUGUAUUUAUUACAUUUUCACGUGUCUUCACGCAUCUCUUGAAUUGGAAAUUGUGCCCUGGAGACUGUAUACAAGACUGGAUUAAAAAGACUGGAUUCUGUUUU